ACAGGAAGAUGGCCAAUCUUUCCUAAGCUGCUCACCUUACAAGAAAACGAAUCGUACUGCUAAGAAUUCAAACUUCAGCAGUCAUGGGGAGCCUUGGAAGGAGCCCGAAUCACUGAUGGAAUUGGACAGUGCAUGGAGAUGGUUCAGCAGGACAAGGUGCUGAAAACUCAUCCCCGUGUGACCUCAAGUAAGCCAUGUAACUCUGUGAACCUGCAGUUUUAUCAUUUUUAAAAUAAAGAAACAUGACAGAUUUUCAUUAUGACACAGAAUGUCAGGUCUCCCAGAUGCCAGAAAAUACAUUUACUUAAAGCCGUUGAUACGUCUUAAAGCGGUUUCCUUACAGUGUCAUUGGAGGACAGUGUGGAGUGCAGAGAGACAUGCUUUGAAAUGGGAUUGAUCCAGUCCUCCUUCCUUCACUACCACAUGAAUGCUGGGCAGCCCAGGGUCAACCCACCGCACCCUCAACUCAGACGGUUACCUGGCACGCUGGCCACAGUCUACCUCACUCUUAUCAGAGUCUGAGCUACUGGCAGUGCUUUCAGCUCUGAGUUCAGGCACCUCGAACCUUGUUUUUGUGGUGAAGGAACCUAAAGUGCUGUGGGGAGUGAUCACAUUUUUCACAACAUCCCUGGCUCCACCUCUUCUGCCACAAACGUCAGCAUGGUGGUAUCAGCCGGCCCUUGGUCCAGCGAGAAGGCAGAGACGAACAUUUUAGAAAUCAACGAGAAAUUGCGCCCCCAGCUGGCAGAGAACAAACAGCAGUUCAGAAACCUCAAAGAGAAAUGUUUUGUAACUCAACUGGCCGGCUUCCUGGCCAACCGACAGAAGAAAUAGUAAUCUAUAGGCUCACUCAUGAAAUAUGAAGAGUGUAAAGACCUCAUAAAAUUUAUGCUGAGGAAUGAGCGACAGUUCAAGGAGGAGAAGCUUGCAGAGCAGCUCAAGCAAGCUGAGGAGCUCAGGCAAUAUAAAGUCCUGGUUCACUCUCAGGAACGGGAGCUGACCCAGUUAAGGGAGAAGUUACGGGAAGGGAGAGAUGCCUCCCGCUCAUUGAAUCAGCAUCUCCAGGCCCUCCUCACUCCAGAUGAGCCAGACAAGUCCCAGGGGCAGGACCUCCAAGAACAGCUGGCUGAGGGGUGUAGACUGGCACAGCACCUUGUCCAAAAGCUCAGCCCAGAAAAUGACGAAGAUGAGGAUGAAGAUGUUCAAGUUGAGGAGGCUGAGAAAGUACUGGAAUCAUCUGCCCCCAGGGAGGUGCAGAAGGCUGAAGAAAGCAAAGUCCCUGAGGACUCACUGGAGGAAUGUGCCAUCACUUGUUCAAAUAGCCACGGCCCUUGUGACUCCAACCAGCCUCACAAGAACAUCAACAUCACAUUUGAGGAAGACAAAGUCAACUCAACUCUGGUUGUAGACAGAGAAUCCUCUCAUGAUGAAUGUCAGGAUGCUGUAAACAUUCUCCCAGUCCCUGGCCCCACCUCUUCUGCCACAAACGUCAGCAUGGUGGUAUCAGCCGGCCCUUUGUCCAGCGAGAAGGCAGAGAUGAACAUUCUAGAAAUGAAUGAGAAAUUGCGCCCCCAGCUGGCAGAGAAGAAACAGCAGUUCAGAAACCUCAAAGAGAAAUGUUUUGUAACUCAACUGGCCUGCUUCCUGGCCAACCAGCAGAACAAAUACAAAUAUGAAGAGUGCAAAGACCUCAUAAAAUCUGUGCUGAGGAAUGAGCGACAGUUCAAGGAGGAGAAGCUUGCAGAGCAGCUCAAGCAAGCUGAGGAGCUCAGGCAAUAUAAAGUCCUGGUUCACUCUCAGGAACGGGAGCUGACCCAGUUAAGGGAGAAGUUACGGGAAGGGAGAGAUGCCUCCCGCUCAUUGAAUCAGCAUCUCCAGGCCCUCCUCACUCCGGAUGAGCCAGACAAGUCCCAGGGGCAGGACCUCCAAGAACAGCUGGCUGAGGGGUGUAGACUGGCACAGCAACUUUUCCAAAAGCUCAGCCCAGAAAAUGACAAUGAUCACGAUGAAGAUGUUCAAGUUGAGGUGGCUGAGAAAGUGCAGAAAUCGUCUGCCCCCAGGGAGAUGCAGAAGGCUGAAGAAAAGGAAGUCCCUGAGGACUCACUGGAGGAAUGUGCCAUCACUUGUUCAAAUAGCCAUGGCCCUUAUGACUCCAACCAGCCACAUAGGAAAACCAAAAUCACAUUUGAGGAAGACAAAGUCGACUCAACUCUCAUUGGCUCAUCCUCUCAUGUUGAAUGGGAGGAUGCUGUACACAUUAUCCCAGAAAAUGAAAGUGAUGAUGAGGAAGAGGAAGAAAAAGGGCCAGUGUCUCCCAGGAAUCUGCAGGAGUCUGAAGAGGAGGAAGUCCCCCAGGAGUCCUGGGAUGAAGGUUAUUCGACUCUCUCAAUUCCUCCUGAAAUGUUGGCCUCGUACCAGUCUUACAGCGGCACAUUUCACUCAUUAGAGGAACAGCAAGUCUGCAUGGCUGUUGACAUAGGCGGACAUCGGUGGGAUCAAGUGAAAAAGGAGGACCAAGAGGCAACAGGUCCCAGGCUCAGCAGGGAGCUGCUGGAUGAGAAAGGGCCUGAAGUCUUGCAGGACUCACUGGAUAGAUGUUAUUCAACUCCUUCAGGUUAUCUUGAACUGACUGACUCAUGCCAGCCCUACAGAAGUGCCUUUUACAUAUUGGAGCAACAGCGUGUUGGCUGGGCUCUUGACAUGGAUGGUGAGUACAUUGAAAAGUACCAAGAAGUGGAAGAAGACCAAGACCCAUCAUGCCCCAGGCUCAGCAGGGAGCUGCUGGAUGAGAAAGAGCCUGAAGUCUUGCAGGACUCCCUGGAUAGAUGUUAUUCGACUCCUUCAGGUUAUCUUGAACUGCCUGACUUAGGCCAGCCCUACAGAAGUGCUGUUUACUCAUUGGAGGAACAGUACCUUGGCUUGGCUCUUGACGUGGACAAAAAGGACCAGGAAGAGGAAGAAGACCAAGGCCCACCAUGCCCCAGGCUCAGCAGGGAGCUGCUGGAGGCAGUAGAGCCUGAAGUCUUGCAGGACUCACUGGAUAGAUGUUAUUCAACUCCUUCCAGUUGUCUUGAACAGCCUGACUCCUGCCUGCCCUAUGGAAGUUCCUUUUAUGCAUUGGAGGAAAAACAUGUUGGCUUUUCUCUUGACGUGGGACUCAGCGGCAUGCUGAUGGAAGUGGAAGAGCCUGAAGUCUUGCAGGACUCACUGGAUAGAUGUUAUUCGACUCCGUCAAUGUACUUUGAACUACCUGACUCAUUCCAGCACUACAGAAGUGUGUUUUACUCAUUUGAGGAACAGCACAUCAGCUUCGCCCUUGACGUGGACAAUAGGUUUCUUACUUUGAUGGGAACAAGUCUCCACCUGGUCUUCCAGAUGGGAGUCAUAUUCCCACAGUAAGCAGCCCUUACUAAGCCGAGAGAUGUCAUUCCUGCAGGCAGGACCUAUAGGCACGUGAAGAUUUGAAUGAAACUAUAGUUCCAUUUGGAAGCCCAGACAUAGGAUGGGUCAGUGGGCAUGGCUCUAUUCCUAUUCUCAGACCAUGCCAGUGGCAACCUGUGCUCAGUCUGAAGACAAUGGACCCAAGUUAGGUGUGACACGUUCACAUAACUGUGCAGCACAUGCCGGGAGUGAUCAGUCAGACAUUUUAAUUUGAACCACUUAUCUCUGGGUAGCUACAAAGUUCCUCAGGGAUUUCAUUUUGCAGUCAUGUCUCUGAGCUUCUAUACCUGCUCAAGGUCAGUGUCAUCUUUGUGUUUAGCUCAUCCAAAGGUGUUACCCUGGUUUCAAUGAACCUAACCUCAUUCUUUGUAUCUUCAGUGUUGAAUUGUUUUAGCUGAUCCAUCUUUAACACAGGAGGGAUCCUUGGCUGAGGAUUGUAUUUCAGAACCACCAACUGCUCUUGACAAUUGUUAACCCGCUAGGCUCCUUUGGUUAGAGAAGCCACAGUCCUUCAGCCUCCAAUUGGUGUCAGUACUUAGGAAGACCACAGCUAGAUGGACAAACAGCAUUGGGAGGCCUUAGCCCUGCUCCUCUCGAUUCCAUCCUGUAGAGAACAGGAGUCAGGAGCCGCUGGCAGGAGACAGCAUGUCACCCAGGACUCUGCCGGUGCAGAAUAUGAACAACGCCAUGUUCUUGCAGAAAACGCUUAGCCUGAGUUUCAUAGGAGGUAAUUACCAGACAACUGCAGAAUGUAGAACACUGAGCAGGACAACUGACCUGUCUCCUUCACAUAGUCCAUAUCACCACAAAUCACACAACAAAAAGGAGAAGAGAUAUUUUGGGUUCAAAAAAAGUAAAAAGAUAAUAUAGCUGCAUUUCUUUAGUUAUUUUGAACCCCAAAUAUUUCCUCAUCUUUUUGUUGUUGUCAUUGAUGGUGGUGACAUGGACUUGUUUAUAGAGGACAGGUCAGCUCUCUGGCUCAAUGAUCUACAUUCUGAAGUUGUCUGAAAAUGUCUUCAUGAUUAAAUUCAGCCUAAACGUUUUGCCGGGAACACUGCAGAGACAAUGCUGUGAGUUUCCAACCUUAGCCCAUCUGCGGGCAGAGAAGGUCUAGUUUGUCCAUCAGCAUUAUCAUGAUAUCAGGACUGGUUACUUGGUUAAGGAGGGGUCUAGGAGAUCUGUCCCUUUUAGAGACACCUUACUUAUAAUGAAGUAUUUGGGAGGGUGGUUUUCAAAAUUAGAAAUGUCCUGUAUUCCAAUGAUCAUCCUGUAAACAUUUUAUCAUUUAUUAAUCAUCCCUGCCUGUGUCUAUUAUUAUAUUCAUAUCUCUACGCUGGAAACUUUCUGCCUCAAUGUUUACUGUGCCUUUGUUUUUGCUAGUGUGUGUUGUUGAAAAAAAAAACAUUCUCUGCCUGAGUUUUAAUUUUUGUCCAAAGUUAUUUUAAUCUAUACAAUUAAAAGCUUUUGCCUAUCA